AUGGUCACAGGUUGGCACUGGGGGCCCAGCCACGUGCCAGCAACAAUUGUCAAGGGCAUCAACAAGUCUGGUGGUGGCAGGAAUGAAAAAGAUGGUGGACGGCUGCAGCCCCCGGGACCCCCGCUGCCCGCCUCGCCCCAACUUCUUCGCCCGGCGCCCGGCGCGCCCAGCCUCGGCCGCAGCUCCCAGCCCCGGGCGCCCGGCCGAGCGCUGGGACCCGGCUCCCGCCGCCGGCACGUCCCCCGGCAGCCACUCGCUGGCGCUGCCUCGGCCUGCGGCCGCCUCCCGCCCCCUCCUCUCCCCGAACCAACAGUAAACACAACUUUUUAUGAAAAGAAAACAAACUUCAGCGACGUGACUCACCUCUGCUGCAGCCGGCGCCUGGGAAGGGCGAGCCGGGGCCCGGGGGCCAGCGUGGUGGGCGCGAGGGAGCCACACAGCGCCGCGCCGCACGGACACACAACACGCUCGGUGACACCGGGGACACACAACACGGGCGAGCGGCCGCGGCUGGAGCAACAAAGGAGCCGAGGACCGAGAAGUUGCGGGCCGGAGAGGGAGGGCGCGUGCGGGCGUGUUGUGGCUGUGGCGGGCGUGAGGGUGUGCGCGCCGUGUGUGCGCGUGUGUGUCUUUUCUGUGUGUGUUUGUGUGUCUCUGUGUGUGUGUCUGUGCGCGCGCGCGGCGGCUGACACCGGCGGGCCGGGGCUCAGGGUCCCCGCGGCAGAAAGCGGCGGCCGCGGGGGCGGCAGCAGGAGGACAACGCAGGGGACGCCGCGCCCAGCGCACCCGGUCCCUCCAUAUGGAAGAAGCUUUUUGGAUGACUGAACUCGCAAACAAUUCCUUCUUUUGCUUCUCCUGCCUAGGAGCCUCCCAUUACCGUGCGAGGAGGAGGAGGAGGAGGGAGUGGAGGAGGCUGGGAGGAGGGGGAGGAGCAAAAUGGAGCAAAGAAAAAGUCUUGGAAAGGAAGCUGGAAAAAGUCCCCCAAACUCUAGGGCAGUUUUCCCGUUAACACCCACUUUUUGCUGUGCCUCAGACCCGCGCUCUCCUCCAACUUCUUUUGCUUUCCCAUACCAAAAGCACCAUCUUCUCCCUUUUCCCCGAACCCAGGGGGCUCCCCUGAAGCCUUCACUUUCUCUUUAGCUUCACCUCGCACCCUUGCUCUUCCAUGUACAAUCCUUCCCUCCUUUCGCCUAGUCUCUUCCAAGACUUUCCUGACACCCACCUCUCAAUGGUCUUCUUCUUCUGCAAGACAAACUGUUGGAUAAAUCAUUAAAAGCAAACUCAUCAGAAAAUGGGACAGCGGCGGUGGAGAAAAUGAUAAGGAAACCAAUCUCAGGGAAGCCUUAACGCAGCCUCCCCCGACCCCCUCGGUCGGUUGGGGAGGGUUUGCCGCGUCGUCCAUUGACAGCGCCCUGACCUCCAUUCAUCAUCCCAGGAUGGAGCCAGGGAGGAAUGGGGAGGGAGAGCUGGGGCUGGGGUUGGGGGCAUGGGUUGGGGGUGCUAGUGGCCACGGAAAAGUUAGUUACCUAUGCGUGUGUAUGUGUACGCGCACGCGCGCGUGUGUGUUGGUCAGAAAACUUUCAGAGCUGUGGUUCUCAAACUUGAUCUGCAGCAGGACUCCCUGGAAGGCUUGCUAAAUCCCUUUGCUGGGCCCCACCUCCAGAGUUUCUGAUUCAGUAGGUGGACCUGGGAAUUUGCAUUUCAAAUAGGUUCCCAGGUGAUGCUGAUGCUGCAGGUCAGGGGCCACGUUUUAAAAACUACCUUUCCAGGGCAGUGAGAAGGCAAAUGUUGAGUUGGUGGCAAAUUGGAUUCCCUUCUUAUUUUUUAGGAAUGAAGCACAGGUUGUGAGCGGUCAUCCAUUCCGUAUCUUCAUUGCAGCUGAGAAAACCAAGUCCCAGCAGGGCUAAGCCAUUUGUUUAAAGUGAACUGGGAGUUUGUGCCAAGCUGGUGAGGAAGCUGUCCUGGAAAUAAGACAGCCAGGCUAGUAGUAGGGUGAAUGGGGGUGCUGCCUUCCCUGUGUGGCUGGACAGCUGCACUGGGAGUCAGGAAGCCACUGUGACUUUGGAAAGUCACUUAACUUUUCUGGGCCUCUGGGGGUUUUGUGUGUGUGUGUGUGUGUGUGUGUGUGUGUGUGUGUGUGUGUGUGUGUGUUUGUUUGUUUGUUUGUUUUUUGACAGAGUCUCACUCUGUCGCCCAGGCUAGAGUGUAGUGGUGCAAUCUCGGCUCACUGCAAAGUCUGCCUCCUGAAUUCGAGAGAUUCUCCAGUGUCAGCCUCCCAAGCAGCUGGGAUUACAAGCACCUGCCACCAUGCGCGGCUAAUUUUUGUAUUUUUAGUAGAGACGGAGUUUCACCAUGUUGUCCAGGCUGGUCUUGAACACCUAGCCUCAAGUGAUCUGCCCACCUUGGCCUCCCAAAGUGCUAAAAUUACAGGCGUGAGCCACCUCACCCGGCCCUGUUUUGUUUUUUAUUAACUUGUUUCUUGUCAGUAAACAUACAUACUUUACACUGAGUAUAGGACUCUAAUUGAAUCUGAACCAAAAGACCUUUACAAAGGAAACAUAAAUGUAUUUUAUUCCAUAUUUUGCACUAUUUUUUCUCCGGUAUUUAGUCAUUCAGGCAGAAGCCAAUUUCCUUUUUGAUUUAUCGAGUACUUUCAGCUCUGUGCCUGGAUUCUUAGGCAUGUUCCUCUGGCAAAAUGGAUCUGGAGGAUGAUGCAUUUUCAGCAAGAAGGUGAAAAGGACUCUGAACUCUCUCUGUGCAUUAUCCACCUACAUUUCCUUUUCCUACUUAAUCAUCCUAAUUUUCCUUCCCUUUUAAUCUCUAACAAUCUCCCCCAACAUUCUCAAAGACCUAUUUUUCUUUCCAGUCAUUGACUAUAUUAGCUUCCACUUUCUUUUGUCCUCCUUCCAAGGCACAAUUCUGGACUACAAGGCCUGGGGUCCACCCUGGGUACAGAACUUUUAAUUCCCCCAAGGGAAUGGGUCAACCAGCUUCCUCUGCAGUGAUAACACUCCUUCUCCCCAGGGACCCAAGCAGCGUAUCCAGCCUUCUGUUUUUCAAAGAUGAUUCCAAGUACCGCUCAAUGAGAACGUGAUGCAUGAAGGUCUCAGAUUCAUUCUUUUAUAUUCCUGUAUAUACUAUUCGUUGCUUGACAUCUCAAAGAUAUCUUCUACCCCUUCUGUCAUCUUUCUCCUAGGACUCUCCAUUCUCUUACUCUGGUCUUUGGGUCCACACAGCCCUAGGCUCUGAGUUAAGCAUCAGAACACAACAGAACACAAAGAAUGUAACAGUCCCUACCAGCACCAUUUAGUCAGGAGAAUGACACACUGCCUUGUUCCUUCAUGCAUGCAGGCUGCUCACCUUUCUUUCUUUCCUUUUUUUUUUAAGAUGGAGUCUGGCUCUCUCACCCAGGCUGGAGUGCGGUGGCAUGAUCUCAGCUCACUGCAACCUCCACCUCCCCGAUUCAAGCGAUUCUCCCUGCCUCAGCCUCCCGUGUAGCUGGGAUUACAGGUGCCUGCCACCACGCCAGGCUAAUUUUUUUUUUUUAAGUAGAGACGGGGUUUCACCAUGUUGGACAGGCUGGUCUCGAACUCCUGACCUCAGGUGAUCAGCCCGCCUCAGCCUCCCAAAGUGCUGGGGUUACAGGCAUGAGCCACUGCUCCCGGCCUGCUGCUCACCUUUCUUAUAGUUUAGGCAGAAUGCAGAUCACAGCUUAAUAAAGAGGACUUAAUUCUGCUGGCGGCAUCAAGCACACUGUUGGUACCUCAGAUAUGUUUAUUGUUUUUAUUGCUCUUUGUAUUAAUGUGAUUGUGUUUAUUACUACUAGUCCUGUAAGAACAACGUAUCUGAAUUUUCUCCCCACUCCAUUUUGCCUGGAGGGUAUUUCUUGCCUAAUUCCCUCCUCCCCUUUCAAUUAGUUUCUCUAUCUUAACCCACCCCAACCCAUUCCAGCAUCUCUAGCCAUUUCAAAACAGUUAGGUGGAGUCUGGAUCUUGUAAGGUGCUUUUUGCUACUGUCCGUUCUGUUGAUGGUGAUUUACCUCUAGCACCUUGCUUUCUUGGAAAUGUUAUGGGCCUCCACCAAGAAGGAAGCAUUUGGUAUGGAAGUGAUCAUCACAUUAAUUUAAAUGCUUGGUCGGGGGAAGGAGUGGGGAGGUGAGUAGGGAUUGUAGGUCUAUAUAAGUCACUAUGUUGCUAGGCUGUGCAGAAUAAACUGGAAGGAAUUCAGUGAAUGACAUGAAAAGACGUGGUUUCCUCUCAGUGUGCUGUAGAUACUCUACCUGUAUCAUAUAAACAGGGAUCUCUUUGACUGUGAAAGAUAUCUGGAGAGGAUUAUGCUGAGAAAAUUAUUAAGAUGUAGACAAGAAAGAAGGACUUGAUGAUGUUUUCCUCUGUUUUAAUAUAAAUCUGCUUUCCUGAUUAUAAAAUAUGUGCACUGACAAAAAUUUAGAAAAUGUAGAAAAACACAUAAAAGAAGAAAAUCAACUUAAAGUUACUACCCAGGGAUAACAUUGUUAUUAACAUAGUGGAGUGUUUUUUCUAGUCAUUUUUCUUUCUUGUUUUUGUUUCUCAUCAAUACAAAUAAACACGUUAUCGACACUGAGUAUAUGAUUCUAAUUGAAUCAGAAUUGAAAGACAUUUAAAGGGAAACAUAAUUGGGGUGAGUUUAUUCAAUAUUUUAUACAAUUUUUAAUGCAUCUGGUAAUUCAGGCAGGAGCCAGCUUCUUCAUUGAUUUAUCUGGUACUUUCAUAUUUUACAAAUUUGGGUUCAUUGUACAUACAGGUUAUCAUGCUUUUAAAUUUAACAUUUUAAUGAUUAUUUUCCCCAUAUGUAAUCUUCAAAAUUUGACUUAACUGCUGUGUACUAUCCCAUCAAAGAGAGAGAUUGUUAUUUAUUCAACCAUUCUUCUAUUGUUACAUAUUUAGAUCGUUUCCAUUUUUAUUAUCAUCCUGUAUUGCAGUUGACUAAACAUCUAGCUAUAAA